AGGGCCCAGGUCGGCCCAGGGAGCACGGAACCAAAGAGCGCUAGCGCCGGUUCGGCCGCCUUUCCAGAAAGCCCGGGCCGAACGGCCCCGCCGCAGAGACUCAGCGCGGAUCGCUGCUCCCUCUCGCCAUGGCGCAGGUGCUGAUCGUGGGCGCCGGGAUGACAGGAAGCUUGUGCGCUGCGCUGCUGAGGAGGCAGACGUCCGGUCCCUUGUACCUUGCUGUGUGGGACAAGGCUGAGGACUCAGGGGGAAGAAUGACUACAGCCUGCAGUCCUCAUAAUCCUCAGUGCACAGCUGACUUGGGUGCUCAGUACAUCACCUGCACUCCUCAUUAUGCCAAAAAACACCAACGUUUUUAUGAUGAACUGUUAGCCUAUGGCGUUUUGAGGCCUCUAAGCUCGCCUAUUGAAGGAAUGGUGAUGAAAGAAGGAGACUGUAACUUUGUGGCACCUCAAGGAAUUUCUUCAAUUAUUAAGCAUUACUUGAAAGAAUCAGGUGCAGAAGUCUACUUCAGACAUCGUGUGACACAGAUCAACCUAAGAGAUGACAAAUGGGAAGUAUCCAAACAAACAGGCUCCCCUGAGCAGUUUGAUCUUAUUGUUCUCACAAUGCCAGUUCCUGAGAUUCUGCAGCUUCAAGGUGACAUCACCACCUUAAUUAGUGAAUGCCAAAGGCAGCAACUGGAGGCUGUGAGCUACUCCUCUCGAUAUGCUCUGGGCCUCUUUUAUGAAGCUGGUACGAAGAUUGAUGUCCCUUGGGCUGGGCAGUACAUCACCAGUAAUCCCUGCAUACGCUUCGUCUCCAUUGAUAAUAAGAAGCGCAAUAUAGAGUCAUCAGAAAUUGGGCCUUCCCUCGUGAUUCACACCACUGUCCCAUUUGGAGUUACAUACUUGGAACACAGCAUUGAGGAUGUGCAAGAGUUAGUCUUCCAGCAGCUGGAAAACAUUUUGCCGGGUUUGCCUCAGCCAAUUGCUACCAAAUGCCAAAAAUGGAGACAUUCACAGGUACCAAGUGCUGGUGUGAUUCUAGGAUGUGCGAAGAGCCCCUGGAUGAUGGCGAUUGGAUUUCCCAUCUGACUUCCUGGAAAUUGGAGCACACAGUCAGGUGAAUUUCUCUAAUGUGAGCUGCCUCAUGCUGGCUGCUGGGGAGAUGAAGGAAAGGAAUUCGGAGAAAAGUAAAGCAUGGAACUAUUCCUAAAGGGAUGAAUGACUAAUUCGCCAUUUGGGACACCCAUGAGUAAACUCAGACCCUCCUAUUACUCAAAAGGGAAAGACAAAUCAGUUAUAACAAGCAAUAUUAAUUGUGCACUUCUGAAUGAUCUCAUUUUAUAUUUAGAACAACACUCUAAAGAAGACUUCUCCAAAAAGCUCCUACAACUGAUAAAUACAUUCAGCAAAGUUAGAGGAUACAAAAUUAAUGUACACAAAUCAGUAGUUCUGCUAUACACCAACAGCGACCAAGCUACGAAUCAAAUAAAACACUCAACCCCUUUCACGAUAGCUGCAAAAUAAAAUAAAAUACCUAGGAAUAUACCUAACCAAGGACAUGAAAGACCUCUACAAAGAAAACUACAAAACACUGCUGAAAGAAGUCAUAGACAACACAAACAAAUGGAAACACAUCCCAUGCUCAUGGAUGGAUAAAAUUAAUAUUGUGAAAAUGACCAUACUGCCAAAAGCAAUCUACAAUUUCAAUGCAAUUCCCUUUAAAAUACCAUCAUUCUUCACAGAACUAGAAAAAAAUCCUAAAAUUCAUAUGGAACCAAAAAAAAAAAAAAAAAAAAAAAAGAAAAACCCUGCAUAGCCAAAGCAAGACUAAGCAAAAGAACAAAUCUGGAGGCAUCACAUUGCCUGACUUCAAACUAUACUAUAAGGCCAUAGUCACCAAAACAUCAUGAUACUGGUAUAAAAAUUGGCACAUAGACCAAUGGAACAGAAAAGCGAACCCAGAAAUAAACCUAAAUACUCACAGCCAACUGAUCUUCGACAAAGCAAACAAAAACAAAGUAGGGAAAGGACACCCUAUUCAACAAAUGGUGCUGGGCUAAUUGGCAAGCCACAUGUAGAAGAAUAAAACUGGAUCCUCAUCUCUCACCUUGUACAAAAAUCUACUCAAGAAGGAUCAAAGACUUAAACAGAAGACCUGAAGCCAUAAAAAUUCUAGAAGAUAACAUUGGAAAAACCCUUCUAGACAUAGGCUUAGGCAAAGACUUCAUGACCAAGAAUGCAAAAGCAAUCGCAACAAAAACAAAGAUAAAUAGAUGGAACUCAAUUAAACUGGUAAGUUUGUGCACAGCAAAAGAAACAAUCAGCAGAGUAAACAAACAACCACAGAAUGGGAGAAAAUUUUCACAAUCUGUACAUCCAACCAAGGCCUAAUAUCCAGAAUCUACAAGGAAUUCAAACAAAUUAGCAAGAAUAAAACAAACAAUCCCAUCAAAAAGUGGGCUAAGGACAUGAAUAGACAAUUCUUGAAAGAAGAUAUACAAAUGGGCAACCAACAUAUGAAGAAAUGCACAACUGAAAAAUGCACAACAUCACUAAUGAUCAGGGAAAUGCACAUCAAAACCACAAUGUGAUACCACCUUACUCCUACAAGAAUGGCCAUAAUCAAAAAAUCAAAAAAUAAUAGAUGUUGGUGGGGAUGUGGUGAAAAGAGAACACUUUUACACCUCUGGUAGAAAUGUAAACUAGUACAACCGCUAUGAAAACAGUAUAGAGAUUCCAUAAAGAACUAAAAAUAGAACUACCAUUUGAUCUAGCAAUACCACUACUGGUAUCUACCCAGAGGAAAAUAAGUCAUUAUAUGAAAAAGAUACUUCCACAUGCAUGUUUAUAGCAGCACAAUUCACAAUUGCAAACAUAUGGAACCAGCCCAAAUGUCCAUCAAUCAACAAGUGGAUAAAAUACAUUGUGGUAUAUAUAUACUGUGGAAUACUACUCAGCCAUAAAAAGGAAUGAAAUAAUGAUAUUCACUGCAACCUGGAUGGAAUUGGAGACCAUUAUUCUAAGUGAAGUAACUAAGGGAAUGGAAAACCAAACGUCAUAUGUUCUCACUCAUAAGUGGGAACUAAGCUAUGAGGAUGCAAAGUCAUAAGAAUGAUACAAUGGACUUUGGGGACUUGGGAGAAAGGGUGGGAGGUGGGUGAGGGAUAAAAGGCUACACAUUGGGUACAGUGUAUACUGCUUGGGUAUGAGUGCACCAAAAUCUCAGAAAUCACCACUAUAGAGCUUAUUCAUAUAAUAAAACACCACCUGUUUCCCAAAAACCUAUUUAAAUUAAAAGAAGAAGAAGAAGAAGAAGACAUUGCCAUUAUUCUCCUUGGACAGAUGAGAAUGCCUAGGCUCAGAAAGUUUAAAUCAUCUGCCUAAAGUAACCUAGUUAGCAAAUAGCUGAGCUGAGACUUGAACUCAGGUCAUUCUGACUCCAGAAUGUGUGGCCUUAACAAUACCCCCCUAUUUCCCAAUCAGUGCAAUUAAGGCAGGUUCAGAUUUUGAGGACCCUGAAGUAAAACAAUUUUGGGUUGGGCUUGGGAGCAGUGGCAACCCUCUUCAAGAAAAAGAAAAAAAAAUGAAAACAAAGCAAACACAGAGUUUUAGAAGGGGUCCCUGCAAAUGAGAGGGGCUGAAGCUACAGCCUCAUUAUCUUCACAGUAAAUCUACUUUUGAUUGUGAUGGUGCUGUUAUUGACAACAAUGUUAAUAUGAAGAAUAAAAAUUAUUCUUCAAAUCCAAAUAUAUGAAAUUUCAUUGGCUUAGGACUUUAAGAUAUUUUUUAGGUAACAAAAUUGUUCUAGACACUCAGAGAUCCCACAUGCCCCCUUUCCAGACACCAUAUAAUUUCUCUGAGUCAGAAUCACAUCCUACCUGCUCAAAUUCUCGUCAUGAAUUUCACUUCCCCUUGCCUCAAAUUCUCUUCAGUUUUCCUUGAAUAUCUAUUGGGUUUACCUCUCUUUCAACAUCUUUAUUAUUAUCAUUAUUAUUACUAUUAUUAUUACACUUACUACUCACAAUGUGUGCUAGACCACAUAUUGCCCUAAGCUGUUUUCUCACCUAUGAAGAAACCUAGUAUCAUUUCCAUUUUUCAGAUGAGAAAACUGAGGCCCUAAGAGAGGAAAUAGUUUGUCUCUGAAAUUUACACUCUUAACCACUUCAACAUAGUGCCUCAAAUAGCCUGGGUAAAUCAGACAUUAACACAAGCAGACUCCAUAGAGGCGAGAAUGAAGUAUAACAAUCAUAAUGUCUUGAUCAAGUACCAAAUACAAGGCUAGAUGUCCCGCGAGUCACAUACUUUGACCAGAAUCCCCUUCUGGCACCUCUGAAUAGUGCAAGAACAGAAAUGUGUUUUCAGUCAAAUCAGCAAUUCUGAGACACGGGAGACCUUGAAAAUGUGUGAUUCUGUGAUGUAAAGUACAGUAUAUUUUUCUCUGGGUUACAAAUUUUGAAAUCCAAAGAGUAAGCUUGGUAGUGCCUAAAUUUACACACUUAUCAUAGGUAUUAUACUUCUUUAGUCAUUAUCAUGAAUUAUCUGUGCCAGAAAGAUAUACUACCCCUGAAAACUAGUAGCCAAUCAGAAAUAGUGUCUCAGGAACCUAGGUGAGGGGUAAAAUUAUGAGUCACACUGGCAUGGCCAUCUUCCUGGGGCUGAAGCACCACAGAGGGUGCCGAUCUGAGUCCUGUUCCUUGAACUUGAAUGUGUGAAAGAACCUCAAAUUUCACUUAUUUAAACCUUUUUAUUUAUAAAUAAAGGCCAUGAGACCUUGAGAUGCCAAAGUUCACAGAGCUAAUGAACAUUGUUCCUUCAGCAGAAUUAAUGAACAGAUUAUGAGGUGAGUUUAGAGGACUUCCCACUGCACAUUCUGCUCUCAUUGUUAAAGACACACUGUUAGGUGCGACACUGGUAAACCUACAUUAAAAAAAAAUUCCUGUCUAUGGCAUAGAUAGAUAUACAAGGCGUUUGCUAGUCUAGACUCUGCCUACCUAGCCACCAUCACUUCCCACAAUUCCCCAGCAUGAAUCCUGCCCAGAAGGUACUCACUAUACCCUCUCCUGCCUCCGCCUCUGUGUAGGUUUUCUCCAGCCGGUUUGCCUUUCUCCUUAUUCUUCACCCUAUGAACUCCUACUCAUUUGUCAAAACUCAGAAGUGUCACCUUCCCAGUGAAGCUUCCCAUGUGAAGACCUCAUUUCCCACUCCUCCAUCUAAAAGAUUACAUUGAUUCUCUUCUGCUCUCUCAACACACAGUUCUUUGGGCUUUUGGCACUUAUCACAUUGUAGUUUGGUUUUUGGUUUGAUUUUGUUCCCUACAUUAAAUUCUGAGCUGCUGAAAGUCAUGGUCACUGUGUUGUUCAUUCUUUUUAAUUAUCUAAUAUGUGGGCACUAGGGGUAUUGAAGUAAAUCAUAACAAUAAUAAUUAACAUUUAAUCUCUACAAUAAUCCUAAAGGGAGGGUGUGGUAGAAGUGGACAUGACCAGUGCUUACCAAGAUUUCUGGUUCUCUUCUUGAAGCUAGGGGUGGCCACAUGACUUGCUUUGAUGGAUGAAAUUUAAGCAGAAGUGACAUGUGUCACUUCCAUGUAUAAUCAUCUAAUAAGAGGUACUCUUUCCCCUUGCAAUGGUGGAUCCUAAAGCCUUGUAUUGGGCAGGCAUCAUUAUAAGGUAGUGAAGGCUCAGUGACCCCCUGCUGACCCAUGUUGGACACAGCAUGGAUGAAAAAUAAAUAUUUGUUGUUUGAAAUCACUGAUAACUGGUGUUUGUUACUGCAGCAUAACUAAGCCUCUCCUGACUAGUGUGGUGGGGGGCAGAGGGUGUCUAAUAUUAUCCUCUUUUUAUAAAUGAAUUGAGGUCACCCAGGUGGUAGGUGGAAGAGGGAGGAUUCAAACUCAGCAGAUGUUAAAGCUUGAUGUUAAAGUUUGAUAUUAAAGCUUAUCUUCCAGAUCUCUAUGGAAUACAGAAAGAGGAAUGAAACCAAUCUUCUUCCAUACUGACCAUUUUAAUUAUUACUUCCUUUCCUGUUUCCAGCCAUUAUCAGAAAUUGGUAGAGCAGCUAUUCCUUCAGAGAAUAUCUAAGCAAAUUCCAUCCUUCUUCUCAAGUCUGUUAAUAUCUCCAUCCCCUAAUUCUACUUUGGGUGUGUUGGGUUUUGCUCACAGCAACUCUGGAAGGUUUGGGCACAUAUAGUAUUUGUCUUUUGCUGAAAGCAAUAAAGAACAUGUCAGCACAUGUUCAUUUUCUAGUUAGAUUUUUAAAAGUCAUUUCAAGAGUUCCUUUUUAGUUUCUGCUAAGCAAACAUAACCUUCCAUUAAAUAGCAAACACAAAUGUUUGUGUGGUUUGCUUUCCUUAAAGAAAUUAUUAUUUUAAAAAAAGUCAACUCUCUUUGCCAGUGGUAUCAAUGAGUUGGUAAAGCACUGAAAUUAGGGAGGAUGAGGAGAAUACAAAUUCAAGGCUAAAGAAAAUAUUAUUGUUUGGCUAAUUCAGCCCAAGAACCCUUCCAACCAUGAAGGCUUAAUACAGAUGCUGUUCGUGAAGUCAGACUAGUACUAGGUAGUGUUUAAGAGCAGGGUUUCAAAGUCAAAUGAGUUCACAUUCAAAUUCUGCCCUUUAUUUGUUCUUUGAUGUGGUCAAUUUAGCUAGCCACUCAGAACCUUAGUUUUAUCAUCUGCAAGAUGGGUAAAUUACAGCUACCUUUGUACAAUUGCUAUAAGGAUUCCAUACUUGCAUUAAUUCAAAUAGAUAAAGCCCUUGACACUAUUGUCUACUAUCUGAUAAACAUUUGAUGAAGAAUAGUAUUAAGUUUGCCAUAAAUAACACCUGUCCAUCUGCAUAGCUUAGGUUAAAAGAAAAUCAGAAUACUGCCACAGGGAAGUGGCUGCAGGACUCAGAGAAACCAGCUCAAGUUUGCUUAUCUUCAUGUUUCCUGUUCUUUGAGGCAAUUUCUUGGUCAGGAAAUUAUGAGGGGGAUUGGUCACAGGCAGAGAUUGUGUUCUCUUGGGAGCCCAGGAGUAGGGUACUGUUAGAAUUUCAUACACAUUCUCUAGGCCCAAACCAAAUUCUUUUUUUCCUUAAAAGUCCAUCUUUGGCCGGGUGCUGUGGCUCAUGCUUGUAAUCCCAGCACUUUGGGAGGCCGAGGCGGGCGGAUCACGAGGUCAAGAAAUCGAGACCAUCCUGGCCAACAUGGUGAAACCCCGUCUCUACUAAAACUGCAAAAAUUAGCUGGGCGUGGUGGCGCUUACCUGUAGUCCUAGAGUUGGGAGGCUGAGGCAGGAGAGUUGCUUGAACCCGGGAGGUAAAGGUUGCAGUGAGCCACGAUCACGCCACUGCACUCCAGCCUGGUGACAGAGCGAGACUUGGUCUCAAAGAACAACAACAACAAAAAAAGUCUAUCUUUAAUUUCUGUUGAAUCCUAUUUAAGUUUUAUGCCCAUAUUUUGAAUCCUCCCAUAUACUUGGAAAAAAUUUGCAUGUUCUACACACAACUCAGUACCUGGCUUUUCACUUUAGAACGCAGCCAGUUGGUAACUAUGCGUGAGAGUGCAGUGAUCCGCCUCACUCAAUUUACAAGUGUGGAAAAUGUGUGCAGAUUGGCCAAAAUUCAUUCACCUGAUUCCCAGAGAUAGACAUUUAAACCGUUUCCAAGUAGAACUUUCAUGCAUAGCCUUUGCGCCCAUAAGCACACAUAAUGUCCACUUAAAUUGAGAAAAUGUGUGUUAGCACUGAAAGUUACCUGGCAUGGUGAUGAUAACCCAUUUCUUUUUGUUUGAAGUACCCAUGUCUCUGGCUCCAAUUAAAAUCAAUGCCCUGUAGAGAUUGAUGUGAUAGUUUCUGCCAAGUUGGAGAUUGGGAUUGCAUUCCUCACUCAGAUAGGAGUGAGAAUCUUUGGAAACUCCUCCCUCUUUUGUCUUUAAGACUUCACUUUGCUAAAUGGACAUAAGUUGAGACCGGCAGACAUGAUUCCCAACCAACUGGUCUUAGCCAACUCCUGUGUGCUUUUCUAAACCAGUGUCUUUGUUGGUGAUCAUUUAAAUAAUGAUAAGUAGAAAGUAACCAGUGUGUGAUAGCAUUUGCUACUGUUCCCACAGUAUUUAGAAUUACAGAAUGAUUUAAGUCUCCACACAAAGUGAAUGUGAGGGAAAUCCAGGGCAUCCGGAAUGCUCUUUAGCUUCAGGGAUUUGAGCUCGCCAGUAACAGAGCAUUAAAGACUGCACUUUGUUGCCCCACAUUUUCACAAUCACAGCAGCAGAGCACCCUAGGUCUCUGGUGAAGGAAUGACCCUGUCUUUUCCAAUACCCAGACAUCAGAAGAGUGGAUGUAGUUCCUAAAACUCCUAAGGUAAGAGUUCCUCUGCAGAAAAUAAUCAAACAGUUCCUACUAUGACCUGAUGGCAGCUUUUAGGCCUGGGGUUUAUUCCCAACUACUGCCUUAUCUCAUCCUGUGGCUGCAACUUAUUACUUUUCUCAUUAUUUCAGUUUCUCUGUUGGUAAAAGAGAAGAAGGAAUGUUUGUUACCAUCAAAUAAUGAUUGCACUUUGCAUGGAGAUCUCCCAGUGAUGGGAGCAGCCAUGAUUAGACAGUUUAUAUGCAUUGUCUCACAUAUUUCCCACAACAGUCCUAGGGGGAAGGUAAUAUUAAUCCUCUUUUUAUAGUCUUGGAAAACUAAAGCUAAGAGAAAUUAACUAAUCUGCCCACAUGUAUCAGAGCAAGUGAGUUGUGGAGUUAGGGUUCAAAACGGACUCCAAAGACUUCUCUGUCCACAAGUCAAAUUAGAUUUUAUUUAAUAGGAUCCAGAAUACAUAAUUCUGAACAUUUAUCUUUAGUGCCCAAAGUCCUUGAGAAAUAUAUGACUAAAAGAAUCUCUUACAGGAAUUUGCACCAAUGUCACCGUCAGUCACAAUAUUUAUAAAGUACCCUUUAUGCCCUGUAUAAUUGCAGUAACAUUUUGCCCUCUAACCCCCCUUUCAGCUUCUCAAAACUCUAUCCUUAUCUAUUGCAUUUUAUUCUCCCAGAAAUACUGUGAUUUCUCAGAGACGAGGAAACUGGCACCCACAGAGGUCAAAGGACUUGCUAGUCAAUUAUAGAGUUUCCUGAACUUUAUCCAGUAAAAUUUCUUGUGGGGGAAAGGGUGUGUGUUUAUGCACAUGUCAUUCAAUUAAUUUCAAUGGAUUUUUUUUUAAGUAAAGGAAAAAGCAUUACAACAAACCACACAGUACAGAUUUGCUUCUAAUGUUAAUGCGCUUCCCCUUUCUUCUUCCAAUUCCACCCUCCCAAAGUCAUUUAUAGUCAUGGAUUGGUGUAUAAUGUUCCACUCCAGACUGUGAAAGUCCAUGAAUUGAAGAUAAUAUCGUAGACUGAGUCCUGAAGUCCAAGGAGUUAGGAAGUGUGAUUUUUUACUUUUAGCACAGGAAUCCACCUGAGAUUUUCUCACUGGCCCUAGAGUCUAUUUCUCUUCCCCUGUUUACCCCAUUACUGAAUCUCCUUUCCUAGCUAUAGGUCUCCCAGCCUGACCAUUUAGAAACUAGGCUCUAGGGAUUCAUCGGCACUGACUGAGUUUGGUUUGUUCCCAGUUGUCAUUCACUUAACAUACUAUCUGCUCAUCUCAGUGCCUAAAACAUUGUGAGCCAAACCCACUCUAUCACCCUAGCCAGCUGCCCAUCAACCUCCUCUGAGGGUAUUUUGUGGUCUCUAAGGAUGCCUUUAUAAGAACUUUAAAUUGGGAGUAAAGCCAAUAUAGUGUGCACGCUAUAUUGUCCUGAUAUGAAUCUGGCAGAGUUCUCCCAUUAAUCCCUUCCUACCAUUCUCCUGACAUGGUAAGAGUCUCUCUUGGUCUCUGUCCUAAAAUUGUUUUACAAUCAUUUAACUUACACUCACAUCACAUCAAUUUUGACAUCGUAAUGUGAUUUGCAUUGAUUUGAGGCUGCCAUCAGGAUGAGCUCAUAACUAUGUCAAAACCUCCGUUGAGUAAAUAAAGAACUGAUUUUGAACGUGGGGAAUGAUGGAGGAUGGAAAAAUCACAGAAAGAGACCAGAAACAAUACAAGCUCAGUAGGGAAAUUUUAGACAUCAAACAUUUUUUUUUUUUUGGCACAACACACCAAAGGUCACUAGUCUCCCACAUCAAAUACACAGACCAUUUUUUUAAACAAAUCCAUUUUAGUCUGAGUCUUGAAACAAGCCUAAAAUAUGUGAUCUUGCAAAGAUUUUAGGAUAAUUUUAAUUUUGUUGUUUUUAAAAAACGAAGGAGGAACUAUUCGAGAUGUCAGAGGAGUGAGGGAGGGUGAAUGGCCCUUCAACCCAUCCAGAAUGGUUGACGUUUGAAUAACUGAUCAUGAAGAGCAAAAUUCCAGAAUCAUAUUCAUUUUCGGGACUAAGAUGCCACCAGAGGGGCAAAGCAGGCUCCAAAAUGUGGCUUUGUGCCUGUUUUUAAAAAGCAAGCAGCCUCUUUCGUACUCAAUUAAGGCUAAGUGUAGCACCCUACACUCUGCCCAAGAUACAGCCUCCAUGUUUAUCUUGGCAACAAUUCAAAUGGAGGUUUGUGAGGGAGGGUUUGGCCGAAGGUGGGCGGACCCCGCAUGAAAAAGUUCCUUCGCCCAUAUCCUCCUGUCUGAAGAAGGCGGAUGGAGACGGAAGGUUUUCAGGCCGAGUUCCCGCCGACCUUAACUGGAAUAACUUGCUCUCUUUCACAUCUGCAGCUGUGUCCUCCUCAGGGAGUUGUCCGACUAAAUGUGAUUUUAAACAUCUGUCAGCUACAUCAGAGCUCCAAAUUUAGCACUCGGAACAUUAUGUGGAUUUGUGAUGCUCGCUGGAGAACACUGGAACCGUAAACCGAGCUCACAUGAGACAGGCGGGUGGUACGCGGGUUGGUAAUUUCAUCUAUGACACAUUGAAUUUGGCUGCACAUUUAUGAAUGUUAUGUAAAGGGAAAGAGUGACCAUUUCCUUGCAAAUAGCUUUCUGAGUUGCCACAAGAUCAAUAUCGAGAAGGGAAAGCCUUUACACUAGGAACGCUUAUUGUAUUCCUAUCCAAUCAUUUGCCUGGAAUUUAAAAAUAUUCCCCACGGGCUGGUUUUGUCUGAAUUCCCUGAAACUUAUUCUCCUCCCUGAGCUGCCUUUCUACUCCAGCUACAACUGUGCUCCAGUGUACCCAUCCUAGAGGAAGAUGAGUUCUGCGUAAUUCUUGAUUCCUGUUUGCCACCUUUGAAGAUGUCCAGGGGCAUGUGAGAAUCCUCACAGGGCUGCUUUCCCUCCACUGGGUUGGCAUUUCUGAAGAGAUGUGCUGCCCUAGGGGGAAACUGUGAGACCAGUCCUUCCACGCAAAAACUCUCUGCUGAAGCAAAUCCCUGGAUGAUUGGCUAGGAAUUCUUAGUACACAUGAAGGUUUGUAACCAAUUCUAUCAAUUCCCAAAAUCAUGGUGCCCUUGAAGACAGACAUGGAGAGACAUAGCCCUGCAAUUCAGCCUUUGUUCCUGAUAAAUGAUUUAUCGUAAUAUCACAGCAGACGAAAACUUGUGCAUUUGCUUUACUUAGGUUGAUUGGGUUAGUACAAAUGCUCACAGCCUCCAACGUCUAGUUGUUCAUUAAGCCUUUUCCACAGAUAGAGUUAGUUUACACACCCCAUAUCACCCCUCUACCCCUACUCCUCCUCCCUUGCUCCCAAGGCAGCCUGUGUGUGCCUCUACUCUGAUGUUAAUGUGUGGUGUUAUUAGGGAAUGUCUUCAAAUGCCUCUGUGAUCUCUAAGGAGGCAGACAUGCUGUUUGAUUUGUCCUGUAUUCCCGGGAUUAAGACAGGCCCAUAGACUGUGGUCAACUAACAUGUUAAAGAUAGUGAAUAAAUGCAUGAGUGACUGCCACUAGUUUGAAAUGUUUAAGAAUAUACCAACUAGAAGCAAUGAAAGGUGGUUCCAGGAGCACAGUUGAUGGCAAGAGGAGAAUUCUUACAAAUGUAUCAUGAAUAAACCACGGCUGGAUCAUGCAGACAUGUUUGUAUGCAGAGAACUGACUCAACACAGGUCUUCCUUGCUGUUGGAGAAAGGGUAGGCCCAUCCGAGGUACCAAACACCAGGCAAGGACAUCCAUAAGCCAAGACACAAGGAAAACAGUACUGUCUAUAUGGGGUCACUUGACGGGGGUUAAGCAGGAAGAGGCUUGUGCCUCAAAAUGUCUUAUUUCUGGCAUCUGAAAUGAGAGUGUUUUAUAUUUAUUCUCGGAAGGCAUGAUGUUUCUUCCCUCUAUUCAUCCCACUUCUGUGAUGACACACUUACCUUGAGAGUCCACAUAGGGAAUAGUUAAGACCAUAGACUGUAAAAUCAGACAAGAUCAGGGUUCAAAUCCCAGUCCACAAUUCAUUAAGAGGUACUAUCUUGAGAAGGUUACUGGAUCUCUAUGUUAGCUCGUUAGGUGAUUGAAGGUAUUAAAUACCCGGUGUGUAAAUAUCUGAUACAUCACAAAUGUUCCAUGUCAUUAAUAUUAUUAUUCUUAUAAUUAGUUUGGACUCUUGCUUGCAAGUGACAAAAAUGAAACAAAGCUGGCUUAAGCAAAAAAUACAGGUGUGUCUCACAGAAAUCAAGAGCAGGAAUAUACCUGGGCCUCAGGGAAGUUCUGUCACCUCUGCCCUUCUCUGCACAUCUGCUUCAUUCUCCUCUCUCAGCUUCUUCUCUUGUUAGGUCCACAGCAUUGUUGGAGAAAACCCACUUCUCCACUCCUAAGCUGACAUGUUGCAGGUUCAGCUACCCAAAAAGAAACCAACACAAGUCCUUUUCCUGGCCUUAAUUUCAUAGUUUGGGGAGAAAGACUCUGACUCAUCUUGCAUCUAGUGCUACUCCUGUUUAUUCAGUGUGGCAGGAGUUAGUCAUAGGUAGAGGCAGGGUCACAGUUACACCAUGGCCCUGGGGGCUCGCUUCAUUGCCAGGAGGCAGGAAGAGAGGGAGGGCAGCUGGAUAUGCUGGGGAGAAAUCAAGAAAUGGACAGAUGCUGCAAAAGCUGCCUUCAAACUACUAUGAGAGUGAGAAUGGGACAUUAAAAAAUGUGAAGAUGUGCAAAAUGUUCUUCUUUAUGAAAAAGUCCCACAUAUUGCAUAUAUAUUAUGAUCAUAACUAAACUCACUUUUAAAGGUAAGGAUUUAUAGAGGACACAAAGAAAUUGUUUUUAUGCUAUGGUGGUGAAUUUUUAAUGCCCUUUGAUUUAAUAACAAAACUUUGUUUAAUGUGGAAAGCUCCUACAAAGAUUAAUAACCCUUGAGCCUUUGCCACCUAACACCUUAGCAAGGAUUAGUUGACAACUGGCUGAGGUCCACGCCCCAGGGGGACAAACCCAGGCCAGGAGGAGGGGAGGGAGGGGGGCAGGAAAAUGCCAAGGGCUCUGGGGCCAAGCUUCUCGUUCUUCACAGUGUGUGGAUACUAAGACCCUGUCUUCCUGGAAAGGCAGAAACCUGGCUUGGAAUUCAGAAGACUCCAUUUUCACAGAAUCUCAGUAAAUUCCAGGCCAGAGACAGGGCAGCUACUAGAAAACUCCUUUGGUAAUAAAAAGGCAUUGGGAACAUUGUGAAAGGGCACCACAUGGUUCUCAGGGCAAGACCAGUGCCACCUUCCAAAGGCCCUACAGACGUCCUAUAGAAAUGUUUCUAUAGAAACAAAUAAUCCCACACCCACCCCAGCAGCCUCUGUGUCCAUCUGGCACCCCUGUCCCCAGUUGCCACCCCUGGAUGCAAUAAGAAUAACCCAGGAAAAGUCUUUCCAUUUAAUCUUUGGCACACUGCAUCUUCCAGCCUGAAUGUCAAUGUGCUGCUGCUUCUAAUGUUUCCCUCAGGGAUUGGGUAGGACAGGUGGUCACUGUCAUGUUAAAACCAAAGACUUAUGAAGCAACUUUGUGAGCAUUGUGAGAGCUUAACUCCUACCCCAGAGACAGACCCCUGAGACUCUUGCCUGGACAGUGACCGAGGCUCUGAAAUACAGUGGGUAAAUCACAUCCACAACCCGCUCUACAAAGUAGACCCAGUGUUUUUGAAAUUGCUCAAGUUCACUGCCCUGAGACAUGCCCAAAUGUUCCCUUAAACACUGCUUUUAUCUUAGCAAGCUCCAGAAAAAUUCACUUCAGCCUAAGGGCUUUGAGUGAGUGUUCAAGGCCCAAAAGCCUGAGUUCUGGUGUCAGAGCCCAUUCCCUUCUGCUCCCAUGACUAUUGCCUUAAUUGAAAACCUUAAUAUCACCAACUUGUGCAACUCAGCAGUGUUUAUCCAGAGCCCAGGCCUCUAUGUCCUAUAGAGUACAGACUUAGAAAGUUAUCUCUACAAUACAUGUAUUAAAUAGCCAUACAUUCACUAAGGUAGUCAAUUAAUUGGGCACCUACUAUGUGCCCGGUAGUGUGAUAGGAGCUGUGUAUAGAAUGUGAAUAAGCUUCAGCCCUGCUCAAGGUACCUCCAGUCCAGUAAGGGAAAUGACAGUGCUGGCUGAUUGAUGUUCACAGGACCAAGGACAGGGUGAUUAGCACCCAUGAGAGAAACUUAACCGGAUCUCCAGGAGUCACACAGAGAAUGUUUUCUGCAGCAGAGGAUAGUACUGCAGAGUCCUAAAGAAAGUUAUAGACUUGGGCAGGUAAAGAUGAGGAAGAAAAUCGAAGCCCCUAGCCCCUCUGGCCACAGCCUCUGCCCACCCACCUCGUGAGGUCUGGCCAUGAUCUGAGUUCAUGAAAACUGCACAGUGUACUUGUCUGUGUGGGAGUUGUAUGGGGGUAAGGGAUUGGACACCUAAAAAUGAAAAUAAAGGCUUUCCCUCUUCCACAACUUGUUAUAAAAUCUGACUUUCUGAUUGACGGCUUAGAGAACCACCAGCGUUUUUUGUCAGAACAAGUGAGGUCAAUCUAAAUAGUUUAUCAAAUGCAUACAGUACCUACUGUGCACCGGGUUGUGGGGGAUGGCACAUAAAUUGGAUAUGACGAGAUAGAGGGAGAAGAGACAAGAGAGAUGGAAAAGCGUCCUGGGGUGGAGUAAAGAAGGAAGGAAAAAGGUCCAGAGCAGGUUAGGUGACCCACCAGCAGUUUGCUAGUGUACCUGCUGAUUUUUAUCUGUGGACCAGCAACUUUAUCUCUUCCCAGACCAAGUAGGAAUGGCUACUUGGAACGAGAAGAAAUAUCAGCAGAGCAUCAUAAGGCUUUCUGGUCUGUUGUCUCUGACAUGCUCCAAAUGUGGGAUAAAUACACUGUGGUGUGGUGCACCAUUGGAAGAGGCUUUGUAGGCCAGGGAAAAGCUUAGCUGACCCAUUUAGAUGUCUCCUGGACCUGGGCCUCAGAUUCAACAAAGCAUAGGUGAAAUGUGGGGCAAAGGAAUCUUCAAAGGGGUCUCAGAGGUUUCAGUUCCAUGAACAUCUUCUCUAAUGCACAUAGUUAAGUCACAAGAAGGUAUUAAAUACUAAAAUGUGUCAUUCCAGCUUUGUGUGUUUCCACAGAUACGUGUGUGUAUGCACGUGGUAGUGUUGGCCAUGUGUGACUUUUGGUGAAUUGCAGACUUUUGUCCAUUUUUACCUGGUGCAAAACUAAAGAGAAGAGAUGCCAACAAACUCCUUAUAACAGCUACCCAAUCCAUUCCAUGCUCUUUGGAAGCCCGUUUUUAUAGAAAUUUAGAGCUGUGGGGCCAUAGAGAUUAAAUGAGAACCUGUUUAUUAGUAUGCUUAGCAUGUGCUGGGUGCAUUAAUCAAUGAUAAAAGAGCUCUUUCAAAUUCCUCAUUUUACAGAUAAAGAAAUAAGUCAUUUAGGUAAAUUGUUCAAAGUCACAUGCUGCUCAUUCUCUCACAUAUAAAUUUUAUGUACACAUUCAUGCACAUCUUACUGAGCACCUUCCUGGUGCCAGGCAUUGUGUGCAGGAUGCUGGCAAACCCAAGUACUAGAAGGCAGUUAUCUGGACUUCUAGUGCAGUGCUCUUCUUUUAUAUGCUGGAAUUUACAUUUAAGAUUUUUUAAGUUAGAGGCAUCAUUCUGCCCGUCAUCUUUAUUAGGGGCUGAGCAGUCAUGGAGGAGUGAUCUCAUUUCUUCAUCAUUAUCUCUGUAUUCCCUCUGAAUAUGCAAGCAUUUUAUUCAGUGGCAAAAUGUGGAGAAAAUAUUUUGAUCCCAAAAGAUAAAAUUAUUAUGAAUUUUAGGUUUGUAGCUUUUAAAACAAUCAAGGUGGGUAGCAUGAAACACAUUUAACAGUUUCAAGUGCAGUUUGCCAUAUUAUUUCAUUCGAUUAUUGUGUAUUUUGUUAUGUUAAAUACACAAUGUUAAAGAGUCUAGCCAGUUAACAAAUUUACAUGCCUCUUUCACGAAUUAUAUUUCUAGGAUGACAUCUCAAGCUAUUGAAGUUUGAGUUAAUGAAGUUAUCUGUGGAUCCUUGCCAGGCAAUUCUAAAUCAGAGGACAUGAAUGAGGGCGGAAUCCGGCCUUUGGUUAUAUUUGGUUUGGCUUGCAGAGUGUUGGUCCACACAAAGUUUUUAAAAUUUUUUAGUUAAUUUGCAACACUUAAAAAUCAGGAAAUAAAAAUAGAGACUCUGACUUCUAAAAAAUAUCAGAAGUUCUUGGAAUACUGAGCCACAUUCUCACUCACUGAUGGUCUGAAUUGUUGAGGGCUGUGCACAGGGUGGCCUUGGUAGACAUGGUAAAUGCUCCCCACAGUCCACCUCACACCCUCUUCUCUAUACCUGUCUGCUUCAUUCAUUUCAUUCAUUUACCUGCCAGGCCCUGUUGGCAUUUGAGUUCAUAGCCUUUGCUUCAUAUCAGGGGUCAAAAUCUUUAUAAAGCCACAUGGAGACUUCCAAAGAAUUUUCUCAGGGUGUUAAGUGCAAAAUGAUUCUUGAUGAUCAAUAGGAUUAGAGUGAAAUAUGCAUUCAUUUGCUCAAUGUAUAUUAUUGUCUGCUGUGUUCUAGACAUGUGCUAAUAAUGGAGGAAACUGAGAUAAAUAAGGCUCAGUCCCUACAGAAGCCUAUAGUCUAUUGAGGGAGAGAAACAAAGUGAUUAGAACACAGUUUAUCCAAAUGCUAUGAUGAGUCACGGUAGCACAAAGGUGGGGACAACAAAGACCAGCUCUAAUUGGGGAAUUUAAGGAACUUUAAUAGCGCAAACAACAGCUGAACUGAAUGUUUAGGGUUCAACUGGAAAAACAGAAAACACUCCAAGUUAGUAAAAUGGGCAGUUUCAUGCCAUGGAUUGGUAACCCAGGGAUGAUGGUUUUAAAACAUGACCCCAGAAAUUUUGACACUCCUUCCAUUCACAGGCAUGAUUUGUGUUUCCACCACCCAUUUGAAUCUGAGUGGACUUGGGACUAUCGCAACUUACAGAAUAGUGGGAAGUGAUGCUGAAUGACUUCAGAAGCUAGUACAUAAAAGAGAGCUUCAGCUUGUUUGCUGAAUGGCACACACACAUUUGGGGCCCUGAACCACCAUGAAAGCAGACUGACCACUCUGAGGCUGUCACACUGUAAGGAAUCAAGCCACGUGUCAAGCUGUGUGUGGAUGCUCUAGCCAGCAGUCUUAGUCUUUGAGUCAUCCCAGCCCAGGCACCAGACAUGUGAGCAAAUAAAAUUCAGAUGAUUCCAGCCCCCAGGUGUGGAGUCAUCUGAGUCUUUGAGUCUUCACACCUGAGGUCCCAGAUAUUGAGGCCAAGAGAUAAACCAUCUUGGCUAUACCCUGUCUAGAUUCAUGACCCAUGGAGUGGUUGUUUUAAGCCACUGAGUUUUGGGGUAAUUUGUUACACAGCAAUAGUAAUCAGAAUUACAGGUUAUGGAAUUGCUAAGAAACCAAACAAGACAUUCCAUAGAUUAGGCAUCCCAUAGAUUAGCAACGGCAGGUAAUGCAGUUCUACCACCCCUAGGCCAGAGAAACAGAGGAUUUGGUAUUGAUGAGGCUCAGGGUUUAGGGUUACCUGGCAGAAGUUAGAACAUGGCUUUUCCAAAAGAGUUAAAAAUGGGAGAAACAGCUGGGGCUUAAGAUACCAUCCAAGGAAAAGAGAAAUAAUUGUUUCUUUCUCUUUCAGCCCUAAUAUCUUCUGCUAUUGCCUUCCAUUGGCAUAACCCAUCCAGAAGCCUACAAAACACAGCCUCCAAGGGUCAUUUGCUUGCAAUACAGAGCAGACGAAGGGAAGGCAGGAAAUGGAUCAGAGGGGACCAGGCCCAGGAUUGGCACACUAGUCUUGAAGAAUGAGUAGAGGGUCACUAGACAGAUAAGGAGAGAUAUCAUUCCAGACAGAAGGAACAGCAGAAGGCACAUGGACAGCAUGUUCAGGAAACUUCAAUUAACUCUCCACAAUUGGAAUGUAGUAGAGAUUCUUAUCCCCACUGUACGGACAAGAAAACUGCAGUUGCAAGAGGUUAAUUGUGGUGGUCAUUUGUCAUGUUGGGAGUUACCUGGGCCACAAUAGCUUCAUGCUUGGGGAAAUCAUCUGCUGUAAACAUCUUGGUGGGAGGGAGGGUACUAUCAAUCAAUAUGGAAACCAAAGGGGCUGACCCCACCUCUGUCAGAGCUAAAUGAUCCCAAUUGGACAUUUUUGCCCAGAACUUGGAAUAUUGAAUAAUACAAAGAUUGAGCGUUGAAAAAUUAUCCAUAGCAUCAGUGAUGGCAUUGGGAGUCCAGCACCACUGGAAAUGAGUGUCCAGGGGCAGCCUCUGAACCCUCCUUGUCUUGAUCUUGGCCCUCUUACCUGCUGUGUGAUCUUUCUGGACUCUUGCUAAUUUUCUGAAUCUGAUCCUCCAGGCUUCCAGUUAAUUCUGUGAACUAUCUAAUACUUUGACAACAAAUGCCUUUCCUGAUUAAGUUAGAGUCCAUUUCUGUUGUUUGCAGUCAGUCAGUACUACAAUAAGUAAGAAUUUGUGCUCUUUGCCACUAUGUAUAACAUUUAUUUUGAGAACAGUAGGUAGAUGGUAAAGUGAAAAUGAAUCCAGACGAAGACUCUAGAUACGUAAGUGUGAUAUAGAUCUUUCUGAACUUGCUCAUCACAAAAGGGACAUCACUUAAUAAGGGAAAAAUUUAAAUUACCAGCUAACAUUUUAUUAAGUACUGUAAUAGUUUCCUACAGCUGCUGUAAAAAAUUAUUAAAAACUUGGUGGCUUAAGUCAACAUGUACGUAUCAUCUUACAGUUGCAGAGGUCAGAAAUCCACAACAUCUCUGAGCUCACAUCAAGGUGUCAGUAGGGCUGUGUUUCUUUCUGGAGGCUCUAGGUGAGAAUCCAUUGUCUUGCCUUUUCCAGCAACUAGAGGCUGCCUGCAUUCUUUGCCUAGUGCCCCCUUUUCAUGUCCAAAGCUAGCAAUGGCAGGUUAAGUCUUUCUCAUAUCUCAUCACUCUGAAACUGACUCUUCUGCCUCUCUCUUCAACAUUUAAAGGAUCCUUGUGAUUAUAUUGGGCCUACCCAGGUGAUCAGGUUAAUCUUAAAGUCAGCAGAUCUGCAAACUUAAUUCCACAUGCAACCUGCUUGCCAGGUAGCAUAACAGGCUCUCAGGUUCCAGGGAUUAGGAUAUAGGAAUCUUUGGGAGGCUAUUAGUCUAUCUACCACAAGCACUUAUUAUUUGCCACUUUUUAAUGUACUUCACUUAAUCCUUACCACAACCCCUUGAGGUAGGCAUUGUUAUUGUUCCUGUUUUACAGACGAGGCGACUGAGACUCAGAGAGAAUAGCUGGCCCAAGGUCACACAGUAAAUGGCAGACUGGGCACUCAAUGCCAGGCCUGUCCAGCUCUGCUAGUCAAUUCUCCGAACUCAUUCUAUUUUUUCUGACCUUAAGGCCUUUAUAUAUGUUGUUCCCUCUGCUCAACCCUCACUUCCCCCUUCUUCAUCUGACUGCCUUCUUCUUAUCUGGCAAACUCCUAAGUAUAUGUCACUUCCUUGGGGUCCUCUCUGAUUCUACAAAUGAGGCCAGCCCCCUCUGUUGCAUGUAUUGUGAUUUUGUUUGAUCAUUUGUGUGCAUUUCUGCCCUUUCUCAGAAUAAAAUGCCCUGUCUUUAUCAGGGCCCUCCAAGCCAGGCUCUGCCCUCCUCCAGCUUCAUCUCUCCUCCACUUUCUCCCCGACUCUGGCCAUUCUCACCUUCUUUCAGCUUGUUGAAGUCACCAAGAUUUUUUCCCACCUCAGGAUCUUUGCACACAUCCUUCCUUAAUCUCACCGUGAUUCAUAACAAAACAAUACAAGUGACAGCUAUUUGGGUCAACUGCUUUCCAUUUUGGCCUAAUUACCAUACGGCUAGAAAAAAUAGUCAAAACACAUGUCAGAUUAGCCUGUGUGAGCUUUAUUUGAUUACAACAGUAACCUCCAUUCUGUAUGCUAACCUUCAUGGCUGGUUACACAUGUAAAAUGGUUGUCUGCUCACAACUUAGACAUCAGAGGGAACGCUGGGUGUUAAGAGACUUGGGAAAUUAUCCAAUGCGUUGAUUUCUUGCAGUAAGGAAUGGUUAAAGCUGUGAUGGCUAUUUUAGAAGGUCUGUCUCUACACCUACUUUCUUUGCUUCCAAAAUUCUAGCCGUGAGAGAGAGUGGGAGGAAAGGGAAAGGAACGGGAAGGAAAAAAAAGCGGGAUUUAUAUAAACAUGAUAAAUCUGUUAUAUUACCUACAUUACACACUGGACGCAUUAAAAAAAAAACAACAAAACUCUCAGUUCAGAACAACUGCUGCAAAUCACACAUCCCUGAUUAUAUGGCAGUAUUCCUGGUGGGAAAGCCAGAAGUAGUGAAGGAUGGAUUUUAGCAUGUCCUAUGUGCUUAUUUAUGGUGCAGCACAUCAUCAAACAACACUUCACAGGCUCUAAGCUGGCAAACUGGAGGGCUUUGAAGAGAAAUAAUGAGCUGAGAGGUUCAUGACAUGCCAUUAAAAAGUUUGUGAUUGGAUUUGGAAAGUCAGAUGAGUCUCCAAGGGAAAGGGACUAGUUCUGAGCUGUUGCACUUAGAAUAUUUUUGAGCCCCAGAGCAGAUAUUUAUGAGAAGGGAGAGUUGUUUUUGUCUCAAAUCCAGGUUCUGACUCUGAUGUGUAGUGAGGAAGCCGCUUUGCACUGCAGACCUGAAGUCCCGGAAUAUCCAUGAUGUCACCUUUUUCUACUGAUCUGCCUGCCACUGCACAGAGGCACGCUAUUAGCUCUGUGAUGUUUUAGCUUAAUUCUCCCACAUGUGGGUUGCAAUUCUAGCCAAAACAAAGUCGGCAGGAGAUUUUAUAGCCACUGAAUUGCUCAAGGUGCUACAGGCUCAGUGAAAUCAGGAAAUUAGGUUGGGAUGCAUGAACAAAAAGAUAAACAGAAAGAAAAAGCAUCAGGAUGGUGGGAUUCGAGGUUGCCUGUUACGUGAUUUCCAAAUCAGGAAUCAAGCCUUCGGUUUUGCAAUGGGUGAUUUGAUGCUCUGGGUUUUCACCUUUGAGAUUUUAAUGCUUUUCUGGCAUAUAUGAUAGAAGAAAGCACCCUGUUCCAGGUGGUGAACCAGAAGUCCCUCUCACUAAAUUAGAAAGGAGACAUUUUAGGAUAUGAGAUCAUGAAAUAGAAUAGUAUUUGAAAAGAAAAAAAAAUGAAAAGAAAAAGAAAAGAAAAUCACAUAUAUGCAAUAACACACAACUAGCCCAGCACAGGGUGAAUUUGUGGUUAAGCCAUUUUUUUCCCAUUGCAGAUGAUACUUUAACUCUUUGAAUCUCAGAGUCCUCCUGCACACAUGCAGCAUGAAAAGACGUUUCUGCGGCUGCCAUCAUAAAGCCAAGCUGUACCUCAGGUUGAAUUAGGAAGGUCCGGGGUUCUGUUAGUGUUCUGAUUCUGAGACUGCAGCUCUUUGCCUGAGAUCAUUCUGCCUAGCUCUCCUCUCCCUGCCAGCGCCUUAAUAACGUAAGCCCAAGACCCUUGCUCUCAGAUCUUUUGAACGAACAAUGGUGCUGGGCAAUCACACCAUAAAGGACUAUUUGUGAUCAUUAGGGAGAAAAGGGAGGGGGGUAAAAUGUUAUGCUAAUCAAAAGCAACAACUGUUAUUUCUUCUUCAGUGCUCUUCACAAAAGUCACAUGGAUGAUGGUAAAUCUUCGAGCUGAUGCCAGAUAAACUCUGAAAUUUUAAAGUAUUUGUUUCAUAUGGGCAAAGCUUUUCCUUUUUUUCCCCUUUUUUUCUUCUCUCCCUUUACCCUGUGGGAAAAUGAACUUAUUUUCAGUCACCCCUGACAUCUGACCACUCAACUGAUCACGAGGACACUGUGGCAAACCACAACUCAACUUGAAAUUGUCUCUUUUAGGCUCGGUUCCUGUACUUUGGAUGGCACCAUCCUUGCUACCCAGCAUUAGCUUUUUUUCUAUGGAGGUUCCAUUUUUACUUUCUUCCAUUUACUCAAAGUAAGUGGUCUUGCUGUAAAGUCUCUCAGUUGGGCUUGUCCUCAAAAUAAACUGAAUGCAAAAAUGACACCAACUUUUCAGCCAAAACCCCAAAAGUGGCCCAUUUACACAGUGUGUCCUUCUUUUAAAAAGAAAGAAAGAAAAAAAAAAAAGCAUGAAAACCUUAAACAUCCUGCAAAGGGGGAAGGAAAAGCCAAGUCUCUUGAUUAAUAUCGAGAUGAUACAGCAGGGUUUAUACAUAUUCCUUCUGUUUGAAUCAUCUUGUUUUUUGUAGCUGUUUUACACCUCCAGGAUCCUGCCAUCUGCCCACUCUAAAGAAACACAGCAAAGCAGUCCAAAAACAAUGGCUGGAAGGAAAUCAUUGUGAUCUAACUCAAGAGAUCAACUUGUCUGCACCCUUUCGGUUACUGCUACUCUUCCUGGAGAGAAUACAGUGUGGUGUGGCCCAGAGGUUCAUAUUAUGGGGGGGCGUUGCCUCCUAAUAAGCCCCCCGGUGCCUGUCACACCAUCGGCUGACAAGACAGAACAUGGUGUACGGAUCUGGCUGCCCUCCUGGCUGAGGAACAAGGAGGAGGAGGGAGUGGGCAGCGCCCUGGGCAGUUAUGUCCUACUCAUAUCUGGUGUGUGUCACUGGAAUAUAGGUCAGCAUUUGCUGUACAACUUGGGGCAGGCUGGAAGCAUGCAGACCCCGGAUUGGGCCCAGGAACCCCCACCCCCACUCUCUUCUUGCCUAAAACAAGUUAACAAGCCCGAAGAGCAUUGAGAGAAGCCAUCAGGACAGAGGAAACCAGCCUUUCCAUUUUGCACGCAAAUGCUGGGGAAAUCUAAAGCUUAGCAAAGGCGUUAUCAGUCCUGGGGUUGGGCCAAGAUGCAGGCUGAAGUUCAGCUGGCCAGGCCAAACGCAGCUGCUGGCUAUUCAGGCUUCCCACAGGGACUUUUCCUCAACUCCUGAUUUAGAUAGUGAAAUGGAUGGGUAAUGUGUACAUAGCUGCCAAGGGUGAUAGGAGAAACAAAAUGACUUUCAGUUACUGAGUAGUUCAGGUGGAGGCAGAGAACACAGAAAAGGUUUUCUUUCCAACAGCAAAGUGAAGUGUCCGUUAAAGAGCUGCUGGCCUUGCAGGGAGAUUAUUACUUUAAAGGAAUAUCGGCAAAUGCUUUAGGCUGAACAUUUGGGCUUGCUUACUUCCGUUUUUCCCCGCAGUUCAUAGAGGGAUAAAGAUAUUACAUGAAUUGGAUUUUUCUUGUGAAUUAAAAUAUCGAUGCCCUGAUUUUUGGUAACGAAUGUUGCCAAGUUUGUGCUGAGCAGACAGAAAGGAGGAAUAGGACUAAGGCUUUGCCUUUGGGGAAAUGCAAAAAGGGUUCACAAAAAAAUGUCCCAUUGAUUGUCCAAGGUCACUGGACUAUGCAUGCUCAAAAUGGAACUCAAGACUCCCAAACUGCAGUGUCUGACUCAUUGUCCUUUGACUAAACCAAUGAAAAUAAAAUGGGUUAGCACAGAGUAUUGUUCCAGGACAAAAAGUUCAGAAAGCCAGCAGAGCUUCAGGGAAAAUGGGAUUUUCUUUAAUUAAGCUGACAUUGAAUGCCUCAGUAAUAAUCUUGUAAAUUUGAAUUUAUCAUCUGCAAAGUAGGCAUAUUUGUGAUUUCCUAGCAUGCAAGUUAACUUAAAAUUUAGUGAGUAUCCCUUAUGUUCCUGGCACUGUGCGAGGCAUUUUCCCACACAUUAUAUGAUUUAAUCCUCACAAGGAUCUAGAGAGUCAGAUAUUAUUAUCACUGUUUUACUGAUGAGACUUAAACUGAUCAAUGUUCCGCUUGAAGUCUAACUGUGGAGCUGGUAUCCAAACCCAGGUUUCCUCACUCCCUUAUGGGUUUGUUUGUUUGUUUGUUUGUUUGUUUGUUUUGACAGAGUUUCGCUCUUGUUGCCCAGGCUGGAGUGCAAUGGCAUGAUCUUGGCUCACCGCAACCUCCACCUCCCAGGUUCAAGCAAUUCUCCUGCCUCAGCCUCCCAAGUAGCUGGGAUUACAGGCAUGCACCACCACGCCUGGCUAAUUUUGUAUUUUUAGUAGAGACAGGGUUUCUCCAUGUUGAGGCUGGUCUCAAACUCCUGACCUCAGGUCAUCCGCCUGCCUCAGCCUCCCAAAGUGCUGAGAUUACAGGCAUAAGCCACCGUGCCCAGCCUCCCUUAUGGUUUUUACAGCCCUUUAGCUGCUUCUUUUAAACAGCAUCUUGUCCUGUGUAAUUCAUAUCGAGGUUGGUUGUUGUAAAGUUUAAGUUCCUAGAUGAGACAAACUAUGAGAAAAAAAACAGAGAUUUUUUUUUGAAUUACCUACUUAGAAUAUUUUGCCCAAAUAUGAAGGUUUUAAAAUGUAGUUGAAUUGGUCAUAAAAUUUUAUCUUCCCUUCUACUUAAAUAGUGCAUAAGUUUAUAAAUAAAUGCUAUGAGGAAAACAUUAUGCAACCUGA